AUGCUGGGCUGCCUGCGACUGAGCUGAGAAGGAAACCGUGCCCAGGGCUCUCGGAAGACCGCUGCGGCAUGACAGGCGAGGAGGCGGUGGUGGUGACCGCAGUGGUGGCGCCCAAGGCGGGUCGCGAAGAGGAGCAGCCUCCUCCGCCAGCAGGGCUGGGGUGCGGGGCGCGCGGGGAACCCGGCCGCGGCCCCCUAGAGCACGGCCAGCAGUGGAAGAAAUUUUUAUAUUGUGAGCCACAUAAGAGAAUUAAGGAAGUACUGGAAGAAGAACGUCAUAUUAAGAGAGAUGAAUGCCACAUUAAAAAUCCAGCUGCAGUGGCCCUGGAAGGGAUUUGGAGCAUUAAAAGGAAUCUGCCUGUGGGAGGCUUGAAGCCAGGACUGCCGAGCAGAAACAGUUUAUUGCCACAAGCCAAGUACUACUCCAGGCACGGAGGACUCAGAAGAUAAGAUGAAUUAGAUUUUCCAUUAAGAAGGAACCUCUUUCUGCUGAUGUCUGAAGAACGGAGAAGAAACUCAAGCUUGUUUCAGGAUUUAAGAUGUGUGCAAAAAAAUGAUAGCCUGUAAUUACUAUUAUUGGUAUUAAUACCUAUCUAUAAAUUAAUCCAAAGUAAUGAAAGACUAUUGGUAAUGUUCAGUAAGUACCUGAAAACAAUAAAGGAAAAUAUACUUA